CCUUCCGCCACGGCCGUCUCUGGAGAGCAGCAGGUAAGUGGUUUCCCGCACUGCCGGUAUCCGCCGCCAUCCGGACUCCCGGGUCCUCUGUGCAGGUUGGAGGAUGGUUGGUUGUGGCGAGCGAGGCUGAAGGAGCCGGGACGCGGGGCUCUGGGCCUCGGGAACUGAGCCGGUACUCACCUCCGCCCCUUCUCCCCGUCGCUGUCCGCAGCCAUGGCCCUACGCUACCCUAUGGCCGUGGGCCUCAACAAGGGCCACAAAGUGACCAAGAACGUGAGCAAGCCCAGGCACAGCCGACGCCGCGGGCGUCUGACCAAACACACCAAGUUCGUGCGGGACAUGAUUCGGGAGGUGUGUGGCUUUGCCCCGUACGAGCGGCGCGCCAUGGAGUUACUGAAGGUCUCCAAGGACAAACGGGCCCUCAAAUUUAUCAAGAAAAGGGUGGGGACGCACAUCCGCGCCAAGAGGAAGCGGGAGGAGCUGAGCAACGUACUGGCCGCCAUGAGGAAAGCUGCUGCCAAGAAAGACUGAGCCCCUCCCCUGCCCUCUCCCUGAAAUAAAGAACAGCUUGACAGAAGCCCUGGCUCUCCUGCUGUCCGUGGGUGGGUGUGGGUGUGUCGGGGGCCCGCAGUCCCCUGUCUGGUGCCCGCUCUGAGCCACACCCUCUCCGGGUGCUGCCUGGUCGUGAAUCAAAAGCCGUGGCCCGCCCACCCUUCCCGGGGCAGCAGGUGAGGAAGCCGCCGUACUGCAAAUGACUUUAAUCAUUAAAUAGCUUCUAUGCCACA